CCUUUGGCUUGGCUUGUCAGGGCUUGUCCAGGAGUUCCGCUCCUCUCUCCAACCGGGGUCCCCCUCCAGCGACCCUAAAGCUUCCCAGACUUCCGCUUCAAUUCCUGUCCGCACCCCACGCCCACCUCAACGUGGAGCGCAGUGGUCUCCGAGGAGCGCCGGAGCUGCCCCGCCUGCCCAGCGGGGUCAGCACUUCGCAUCAAGGCCCAAGAAAAGCAAGUCCUCCAGCGUUCUGAGCACCCGGGCCUGAGGGAAGGUCCUAACAGCCCCCGGGAGCCAGUCUCCAACGCCUCCCGCAGCAGCCCGCCGCUCCCAGGUGCCCGCGUGCGCCGCUGCCGCCGCAAUCCCGCACGCGUCCCGCGCCCGCCCCACUUUGCCUAUCCCCGGGACUAAGACGGGGCUAGAGAGCAUAAGCACUGCCUGCAGCCUAACAUCUUGGCUUCUCCAUGAAGAAUACCAUAUUUUUUAAACUUUCCAGAAAAUAACUGAAAAGGAAUCAUCAGAUCAGGCUCUCCCCUCCCAUGGUCUCCCAUUAUUGCCUCUGAUCAGGUCUGAAGAAUCCUGUGAAGCAGCUCCAGCUAUGUGUGAAGAAGAGGACAGCACUGCCUUGGUGUGUGACAAUGGCUCUGGGCUCUGUAAGGCCGGCUUUGCUGGGGACGAUGCUCCCAGGGCUGUUUUCCCAUCCAUUGUGGGACGUCCCAGACAUCAGGGGGUGAUGGUGGGAAUGGGACAAAAAGACAGCUACGUGGGUGACGAAGCACAGAGCAAAAGAGGAAUCCUGACCCUGAAGUACCCGAUAGAACAUGGCAUCAUCACCAACUGGGACGACAUGGAAAAGAUCUGGCACCACUCUUUCUACAAUGAGCUUCGUGUUGCCCCUGAAGAGCAUCCCACCCUGCUCACGGAGGCACCCCUGAACCCCAAGGCCAACCGGGAGAAAAUGACUCAAAUUAUGUUUGAGACUUUCAAUGUCCCAGCCAUGUAUGUGGCUAUCCAGGCGGUGCUGUCUCUCUAUGCCUCUGGACGCACAACUGGCAUCGUGCUGGACUCUGGAGAUGGUGUCACCCACAAUGUCCCCAUCUAUGAGGGCUAUGCCUUGCCCCAUGCCAUCAUGCGUCUGGAUCUGGCUGGCCGAGAUCUCACUGACUACCUCAUGAAGAUCCUGACUGAGCGUGGCUAUUCCUUCGUUACUACUGCUGAGCGUGAGAUUGUCCGGGACAUCAAGGAGAAACUGUGUUAUGUAGCUCUGGACUUUGAAAAUGAGAUGGCCACUGCCGCAUCCUCAUCCUCCCUUGAGAAGAGUUACGAGUUGCCUGAUGGGCAAGUGAUCACCAUCGGAAAUGAACGUUUCCGCUGCCCAGAGACCCUGUUCCAGCCAUCCUUCAUCGGGAUGGAGUCUGCUGGCAUCCAUGAAACCACCUACAACAGCAUCAUGAAGUGUGAUAUUGACAUCAGGAAGGACCUCUAUGCUAACAAUGUCCUAUCAGGGGGCACCACUAUGUACCCUGGCAUUGCCGACCGAAUGCAGAAGGAGAUCACGGCCCUAGCACCCAGCACCAUGAAGAUCAAGAUCAUUGCCCCUCCGGAGCGCAAAUACUCUGUCUGGAUCGGUGGCUCCAUCCUGGCCUCUCUGUCCACCUUCCAGCAGAUGUGGAUCAGCAAACAGGAAUACGAUGAAGCCGGGCCUUCCAUUGUCCACCGCAAAUGCUUCUAAAACACUUUCCUGCUCCUCUCUGUCUCUAGCACACAACUGUGAAUGUCCUGUGGAAUUAUGCCUUCAGUUCUUUUCCAAAUCAUUCCUAGCCAAAGCUCUGACUCGUUACCUAUGUGUUUUUUAAUAAAUCUGAAAUAGGCUACUGGUAA